AGCUGAGAUGGCACCACUGCACUCCAGCCUGGGUGACAGAGCAAGACUCUGUCUCAAAAAAAAGAACUCUGUCACUUGAUAAAUAUGUGUUUUCAGGAACUCUUAACAUUCAGGGAUGUGGCCAUAGAAUUCUCCCCAGAAGAGUGGAAAUGUCUGGAUCCUGCCCAGCAGAAUGUAUAUAGAGAUGUGAUGUUGGAGAACUAUAGAAACCUGGUCUCCCUGGGUGUUGCUCUCUUUAACUCAGACCUGAUCACCUGUUUGGAGCAAAGAAAAGAGCCCUUUAAUGGGAAGACACAUGAGACAGUAGCCAAAGCCCCAGGUAGGUGAGAGUGAAUGAAGGAGAGGACACAGGCAAGGGGACCAAAGGUGAUGAAGGAAGUCAGGCCUUAAAAUGUACUUUGGAAAGCACUUCUUCAAUGCAAAUAAUUUCUGAAAAGGCUGCAUUUUUUCUCAUGUUCACAAAUAGGGGCAUCUUCAGCCCCAUGCUGUUAAAUCUUCUAAAAAUUCUCUUUUUUCUUUUUUUUGAGAUGGAGUCUUGCUCUGUCACCCAGACUGGAGUACAGUGGUGUGAUC